CUUUCUUUUUUUUUUUUUUUUUUUUUUUUGCGAUGGAGUCUCGCUGUGUCACCCAGGCUGGAGUGCAGUGGUGUGAUCUUGGCUCAGUGCAACCUCUGCCUCCCGGGUUCAAACGAUUCUCCUGCCUGAGCCUCCUGAGCAACUGGGACUACAGGUGCCCGCCACCACGCCCAGGCAGAGAAAACAAAAGCUCAGCUGGAAGACACUGAAAUGGAGGCACCUACUUUCAAGCCCAGACUUUAAGAGAGGAGGCUAUGAGGCUCACUGGUCUCCAGAAAUGUACCUCUGUGUGCGGGAAUGUUCCAGAAGGCCACACUGUCUACAGGGCCAUUGCUUCACUGCAGAUUAGAUGUCCUCCCAGAACCUUCCAGGGCACUAAUUGCCUAAACAGCUCUGGCACAGCUGUCACCAAGAGAAGUCCUACUUUGAAAAGCAGAUGGCAGGAGUUUUGAAUACAAAAAAGGAGUUGCCUGGGCAGAUGGCAGUAGACAAGGCAUGAAGAAAUGAAGGUCUCAACAGAGACGCAAGAGGCAGAACAGAAUAUGUAAGAACAAGGGUUCAAGAAGAGGGAGACAUGAGCAAAGUCCUGGCUUCAGAGAGUCAGUAGCCGGGGAUCUGGUAGAGAGUCCCUGCCUCUGGGAUGAGCCCUUCCUCCACAAAAUAUCUGUCCAGCCAUACUCCUCAGUCAGACAGCACUGUGAAGGUUCACAUGGCAUUUCGUAAAGCCUGUGGGGCUCCCCCAAAACACUCUUCCCUAUCCAUCUGGCAAACAUUACUGUCAAAUGUAUCAAAAACUUAUCAUAUAACACUUCCAGUUUUUUCAUCAUAAGCCCUUCCAAACUGCCUGCUGCUAUUGUUAAUGACUGAAGAUUCUGACAUCUCCUUCAUGGAACAAACUCCAGCUCUCUUUUUUUCUUCCUACUUACCUUACUUAGUAAAUUUCAAUAUAUUUUCAUGCAAAUGUUAGAACCUAUGCCUUCUACUUUUCCUUCGAAAUGCUCUUGGCUCUUGCAACUACAGCUGUGUAACUCCAUAGCGGAUGAAACCAUCACAAUCUAGAAAAUCAUUUCUCUGUCUUUUGGACAAGAUUUCAUUUGAUUUCAGAAUCAUCUCCUGACUAUCCAGUGGGCUUGCCUGCAAAGAAGUAUGAUUCUCAAGGAUACAUUUGUUCCAUUACAACUUUUUGUAUGAUACUUGGGUUUAUAACAAAGCUCAGAAAAUACUAAAGGUUAAAGGAGAAUUGAGAGCUGCCAAGGAAAUGAAAGAUGAGGCGGGGGAGAGAGACAGAGAAGUGAGCAGCCUGAACAGCAAGCUGUUAAGCCUGCAACUUGACAUCAAGAAUCUGCACGAUGUCUGCAAGAGACAGAGGAAGACCUUGCAGGACAAUCAGCUCUGCAUGGAGGAGGCAAUGAACAGCAGCCACGACAAGAAGCAAGCACAGGCAUUAGCAUUCGAGGAGUCAGAGGUGGAAUUUGGGUCCAGUAAACAGUGUCAUCUGAGACAACUCCAGCAACUGAAGAAAAAAUUGCUGGUCCUUCAACAAGAACUGGAGUUUCACACAGAGGAGUUGCAGACUUCUUACUAUUCUCUCCGCCAGUAUCAGUCCAUCCUAGAGAAGCAGACUUCCGACCUGGUUCUUCUGCACCAUCACUGCAAACUGAAAGAAGAUGAGGUGAUUCUCUAUGAGGAGGAAAUGGGAAAUCACAACGAGAACACAGGGGAGAAGCUCCAUUUGGCGCAGGAGCAACUCGCCUUGGCCGGGGACAAGAUCGCCUCUCUAGAGAGGAGCUUAAACCUCUACAGGGAUAAAUACCAGUCUUCCCUGAGCAACAUCGAGUUACUAGAAUGCCAAGUGAAGAUGUUGCAGGGGGAACUCGGCGGGAUCAUGGGUCAGGAGCCUGAGAACAAGGGUGAUCAUUCAAAGGUACGGAUAUACACUUCUCCUUGCAUGAUUCAAGAGCAUCAGGAGACUCAGAAACGACUGUCUGAAGUCUGGCAAAAGGUCUCUCAACAGGAUGAUCUCAUUCAAGAACUUCGAAAUAAGCUGGCCUGCAGUAACGCUUUGGUUCUGGAGCGUGAAAAGGCUUUGAUAAAACUACAAGCCGAUUUUGCUUCCUGUACAGCCACCCACAGAUACCCUCCUAGCUCCUCAGAAGAGUGUGAAGACAUCAAAAAGAUACUGAAGCACUUGCAGGAGCAGAAAGACAGCCAGUGCCUGCAUGUGGAGGAGUACCAGAACCUGGUGAAGGAUCUGCGCGUGGAACUAGAGGCCGUGUCGGAACAGAAGAGAAACAUCAUGAAGGACAUGAUGAAGCUGGAGCUGGACCUGCACGGACUGCGGGAGGAGACAUCUGCCCACAUUGAGAGGAAGGAUAAGGACAUCACCAUCCUGCAGUGCCGGCUGCAGGAGCUGCAGCUGGAGUUCACCGAGACCCAAAAGCUCACUUUGAAGAAAGACAAGUUCCUCCAAGAGAAAGAUGAGAUGCUGCAAGAGCUGGAGAAGAAACUGACACAGGUUCAGAACAGCCUCCUGAAAAAGGAGAAGGAGCUGGAGAAGCAGCAGUGCAUGGCCACAGAACUUGAAAUGACAGUCAAGGAGGCUAAGCAGGACAAGUCCAAGGAGGCGGAGUGCAAGGCCCUGCAGGCUGAGGUCCAGAAGCUGAAGAACAGUCUCGAAGAGGCCAAGCAGCAGGAGAGGCUGGCUGGUGAGGCCCCUGCAGCUCAGCAAGCAGCCCAGUGCAAAGAAGAGGCUGCACUGGCAGGCUGUCACCUGGAGGACACCCAGAGGAAACUGCAGAAGGGUCUCCUCCUGGACAAGCAGAAGGCAGACACCAUCCAGGAACUACAGAGAGAACUUCAGAUGCUGCAGAAGGAGUCCUCGAUGGCUGAGAAGGAACAAACCUCCAACAGAAAACGGGUGGAGGAGCUGUCAUUAGAACUCUCUGAAGCCCUGAGGAAGCUUGAAAAUUCAGACAAGGAAAAGAGGCAGCUUCAGAAGACAGUGGCUGAGCAGGAUAUGAAAAUGAAUGACAUGCUUGAUCGUAUCAAGCACCAGCACAGGGAGCAAGGCUCCAUCAAAUGCAAGUUAGAAGAAGAUCUUCAGGAGGCCACAAAGCUUCUGGAGGACAAACGGGAGCAGUUGAAGAAGAGCAAAGAGCAUGAGAAGCUGAUGGAGGGAGAACUUGAAGCUUUGCGGCAGGAAUUUAAAAAGAAAGACAAGACGUUGAAAGAGAAUUCCAGAAAGUUGGAGGAAGAAAAUGAGAAUCUCCGAGCAGAGCUACAGUGUUGUUCUACACAACUGGAAUCCUCUCUCAACAAAUACAACACCAGCCAGCAAGUCAUCCAAGACUUGAAUAAAGAGAUAGCCCUUCAGAAGGAGUCCUUAAUGAGCCUGCAGGCCCAGCUGGACAAAGCUCUGCAGAAGGAGAAGCACUAUCUCCAGACUACCAUCACCAAAGAAGCCUAUGAUGCAUUAUCCCGGAAGUCAGCCGCCUGCCAGGAUGACCUGACACAAGCCCUCGAGAAGCUCAAUCACGUGACCUCAGAGACAAAGAGCCUGCAGCAAAGCUUGACACAGACCCAAGAGAAGAAAGCUCAGCUGGAAGAGGAAAUCAUUGCUUAUGAGGAAAGGAUGAAAAAGCUCAAUACGGAAUUAAGAAAACUGCGGGGCUUCCACCAGGAGAGUGAGCUGGAGGUGCACGCCUUUGACAAGAAGCUAGAGGAGAUGAGCUGCCAGGUGCUGCAGUGGCAGAAGCAACACCAGAAUGACCUCAAGAUGCUGGCAGCCAAAGAGGAGCAGCUCAGGGAGUUCCAGGAGGAGAUGGCCGCCUUAAAAGAGAACCUCCUUGAGGACGAUAAGGAGCCCUGCUGCCUGCCCCAGUGGUCUGUGCCCAAAGACACCUGUAGGCUCUACCGAGGGAAUGAUCAGAUUAUGACCAACUUGGAGCAAUGGGCAAAACAGCAGAAGGUCGCCAAUGAGAAACUAGGAAACCAGCUCCGAGAGCAGGUGAAAUACAUUGCCAAGCUGAGUGGCGAAAAGGACCACCUCCACAGUGUAAUGGUCCACUUGCAGCAGGAAAACAAGAAGCUGAAGAAGGAGAUAGAAGAGAAGAAGAUGAAAGCCGAGAACACAAGGCUAUGCACCAAAGCCCUAGGCCCGAGCAGAACGGAGUCCACACAGAGGGAGAAAGUGUGCGGCACCUUGGGCUGGAAGGGGUUGCCCCAGGAUAUGGGUCAAAGAAUGGACCUCACCAAGUACAUCGGGAUGCCCCACUGCCCGGAAAUAGGAAAACUCAACCUAAAACUCACAUGGAAUCUUAAGGGAUCCCAACAGCCAAAACAGUCUCAAAAAAGAAGAACAAAGCUGAAGAACUUACUGACUUCAAAACUUACUACAAACCUACAGUAAUCAAAAUAGUGUGGUACUGCCAUAUAAAUCAAAAGACAGACAUACAAACCAAUGGAAUAGACUAGAAAGAAUCCCAGAAAUAAACCCUCACAUAUAUGGUCAAAUAAUUUUGACAACGAUGCCAAGACUAUGAAAUGGGGAAAGGAUAGUUUUUGUUUUAGUUUUCCAACAAAUGGUGCUGGGAAAACUGAAUAUUUGCAUGCAAAAGAAUAAAGCUGUGCCCUUACCUAAUACCUUAUACAAAAA